ACUAGACUGCAUUACAAACAGACGAUACCAUCGCUUCAGCAGCAUCCUCUCAGACAAGAGGUAGGUUUAUAUGAUCUUUUUUAUUUAGUGGUACAUGUCCUUAUGAUGCAAUAGGAAAAUAUUUUACCCUGAAAAAUCAACCAGAAAGCUUUGCUCCUACUAAAUAUCAAGAAAAAGCAAUGUAUUCGUUUCACCGCUUGGUAGGAUUUUAUUAUGAAAAUAUGAAGACUGCCUUGUGCUAUUUGAUAAGCACCCUUACCAUCUGUGCCUUAAUGGAAAAUUCAUUACAUUUUACAUGAACCUGAUCUAUAUCCAGACCUCAGAGUAAACCAUAGCUUUUUAUUUUAACUGGUUACUUGCUAAUUUCAUUUUCUCUGAGCGAUUUCAUUUCUGCAGUUUGGUCUGUCUUAACAAAGGAUUUUUCUUAAAGAAAAACCCAGAUCAAAAGCGAAUUCCAGACUAAAGCUUUCUGAUUCUAUGUGCAAAUGAUAUUGGCUGCUAAAAAAUAGUUACUUAUAAGAAAGUUUGUUAUAUUUUUUAGAAUAUGAGAAAAUAGUUCAAAAUUAUUUUUAUUUUGCUUUGAAUGUAGAUGCAGAGAAUGCCAAGAAAUUAUCACAAUUUUAAUUUUUAUAUAAAAGAUCAUAAAAGGUAUCACUAUAUGGGCUGCAUUAUACUACACUGAACAGAUAAUUUAUACAGCUUCAGACUUCCUUAACAUUUAAUUAAAGUAUUUCUUCACUGUGAAAUUUCUCUCUCGUAAUAUAAAGUCAUGCUAUUAAACAAAAACCUUCUUAAAUAGCCUUUCAUUUUUGAUAUCAAUUUAUCACACCAUUUAAAUAUAAUGUUGAAGUCAUUCUUAAACUGAUCCUCAAAAUAAAUACAAAGUAAGUCCUUUUGAUAAACUGCAUUUUAAAAUAAAAAUAUGUCCUAAGAAGAACUGGUUAAGAAAGGAGAGUAAGUACCUUUCUAGGUAACAAGAUUAUCUUCGUGGCUCAGAGCAAUCAUUCAUGUCUAUUAAAAAUUAAUAUUAACUGCUGACCAAAUUUCUAAUUUUAUACUAUUCAAGCAUGAAAAUUUAGUUAUUUACUAGAUGUUAGAACUCCAUCUAUAUACUAUAUCGGACCUAAAGAGCCAGCUUCUGUCCUUUUACCUUGCUGGUAAGUUUAUUUAAUCUUUAAAGGGUUUUUGUUUUUUUUUUCUUCAUAAUUUCUAUUCCUUUUCUUAGUCGGCAUUCAGCUAGCCUGAGCAAAGUAUCCCCUGCAAAACCCAAAGGUUGCUGUAAUAAGAUACUAGAUCUGUCCAGGUUCAGCACAGUGGGGUUAAUUAUCUAGAAACCAUUUGUGCUUGCUACAGAAAGUACAGAAGCACCAAACAAAAGUCUCAGAUAAAAUAAAAAUAACUUUGUCAAAUAAAACAGUUAACUUACAAAUCAAAUUUCAGGUAAACUGUCAACAGAAACCCCUACCACCCACAUUGUUUUAACACUCUAUCAUCAGCCUGCAUUUUGCUUGGAAUAUGUCUAUUGUUAGCACAGAUGGAGGCUCAUUGCUGUUUCACCAAACUGACUGGAGACAUGGCCUAAGUUCCAGAGCUUAAAUUAAGUGAGUUGCUCUAUAUUUACAGGCUAUUAGGAUUAACUGAUCACAUUUCAAAGUGAUAUGCUUAAAAGCACCUGAGAAUUCAAUUCAAAGGCUUUUACCAUAAAUACAGCAAAAGCAUAACUUUAUUCUCAUCUGGCAACCCAAAGGUUCCAGAACAGUUCCAAGUCCCAUCCCCAUUAACACUGCACUGGGGCCUUUGGGAGUAAACAUAUCAAAUGGGAGUAAACAUAUCAAAAUGGGAGUAAACAUAUCAAAUGGGAGUAAACAUACCAAAAUUAACAUAAAACAAAACUAAAACACAUAUGCUAAAAAAAAAUUAUGUGAUUUACUUUAAAGCUCCCCAUUCCUGUAAUCAAAUUUUAAGGCAUGGGUAGGGAAGUCCAGAAAAAGAUUGUUUUACCUUUUUUUAUAUACACCAUUUUCUCUUGCUUUUCAUAAAGAAUGUUUACAGCAUUUGCUUAAUAUAAACUUACAUUUUAAUUUCAAAACUAAGUCGCAGGAUAGGAGAAAAUCCUAAUGAUGUAUUUCUAUUUUUUGGCGGGGGGACGGAGUCUCACUCUAUCGCCCAGGCUAGAGUGCAGUGGCGCAAUCUUGGCUCACUGCAACCUCUGCCGCCCAGGUUCAUGAGAUUCUCCUGCCUUGGCUUCCUGAGAAACUGGGAUUACACACACCCGCCACCACAACUGGCUAAUUUUUGUGUUUUUAGCAGAGACGGAGUUUCGCCAUGUUGGUCAGGCCAGUCUUGAACUUAUGACCUCAGGUGAUCUGCCUGCCUCAGCCUCCCAGAGUGCUAGGAUUACAGGCCUAAUGGUAUAUUUCUUUCUGCAUGCUUAAUUAUGCCUAAUCCAUGAAAGUAAGAUUUAGCCUUUACCCUAAAUUAAACAUCAAAAGUUACUAGAGCUCUACCACACUUUGAAAGAACAUGCCACACUAAAUUUAAGGUGGAAAAUGACUCCAUAUUAGAGAGUUUACUUUUUUCAGAUAUGCCCAGAAGCUAACAAACAAUGAAUGUUUUGAGCCGCUCGGUUAUCAAUACACUCACAAGACAAAUCAUCAUCAUUUACAACAUAAACCUGACCUAUACACUUUCUUAAACUGCUUAGACACUUCCAGCAAAGCAUGUAAGUGCCUUUGGAGGUGGCCUAUGGUGUUACCUAUAGUUAUUAUUAAAAGCGUAAUUUGUUUUGGUUUGGUUUUUUUGAGACAGGGUCUCACUCUAUCACCCAGGCGGGAGUGCAAUGGAGAAAUCACAGCUCACUGCAACCUCAACCUCCUAGGCUCAAGCUAUCCCCCCACCUGAGCCUCCCAAGUAGCCGAGACUACAGGCGCAGGCUAUCAUGCCCAGCUAAUUUUUAUUUUUGUAGAGACAGGGCCUCCCCACAUUGCCCAGGCUGGUCUCAAACUCCUGGGCUUGGCCAGGCGCGGUGGCUCAUGCCCGUAAUCCCAGCACUUUUGGGAAGCCAAGGUGGGUGGAUUACCUGACGUCAGGGGUUCAAGACCACCCUGGCCAACAUGGUGAAACCCCAUCUCUACUAAAAAGACAAAAAUUAGCUGGGUGUGACUGUACAUACCUGUAAUCCCAACUAUUCGGGAGGCUGAGGCAGGAGAAUCACUUGAACCAGGAUGCAGAGGUUGCAGUGAGUCAAGAUUGUGCCACUGCCAUCCAGCCUGGGUGACAGAACGAGACUCUGUCUCAAACCAAAAACAAACUCCUGUGCUCAAGUGAUCCUCCUGCCUCAGCCUCCCAAAGUGUGGGGGUGAAGGCAUAGGCCACAGCACCCAGCCAAGCAUAAUUAUUAAAAGCAUUUUUAUGUGUGAAUAAAGUAUACAGUCUAACAAAAAUGACAGUGUUUCCUAAUCCCAAUUUGAAUUUUUUGGAAUCCAGAAUACUCAAUAAAUGUAUUAAAUAGAUACAUAAACAACAGGCUCUUUUAAGUGAAAGUAAGUUUAUUAAGAAAGCAAAGGAAUACUCAGCAGCACUUUAGAAGUUUUAUUAGGCUAACGUUUUGUAUUACAGUGCAUUAAAUAAGUCAAUAUUGACAGCUGAUUUAACUAGAUGUGUUACAUUUUGAAAGCACAAAGGGAUUUUAUCUUUUUGAAUUAAAGGAGAAAAGCCAAAAAAAAAAAAAAGGAAAGGAAUAAAAGAAUGGUUACUCCAUACUACUCCAUAAGCAGGAAUAAAAGAAUGGUUACUCCAUACUAAUCCAUAUUGUUGGCUAACAAUAGACUUUUAAGAGAGCCAAGAAUAAGGAAUAGUGCUUUUUAUUUCUCUUUUUAAAAUAGAUGAUUUACUUUGGUUUCAAAUAAAUAAUAUAUUUAAAUUGUUGAAAAAACAAAAGAACACAAGGUACAGGUUAAGAAGCCUCAAACAUAUCCCUGUGCCUCACUCUCCUCCCGAUGGAUCCCCAUCCACACCAUCAUUGUGAUUAAUUUCUUGUAGGUCUUUCUAAGAUUUCUCUGCAGAUACAAGCAAAUAAGAGUAUAUGUUUUCCCUCUUCCUAUAUACACUAUCCUACACCUUGUUCUUUUCACUUAAGAACAUAUCCUAAAUAUCUUUCCUAAAACUCAGUUACCUAUGAUUCAAUUGUGUGAAUAAACUAUAUUAAUUUAACCAGAAGAAUAGCUCAUUAAUGGAUACAAGUUAAACCUCAAAUAACUGAAUUUAGUUAUGUAUCUGUCUGCCUUCCUGACUGCCUCUUUCUAUUUAUUUUUGAGGUAAGGGGACCUGAAAAUAUUUUAAGCAGUUCACUUAUACCUCAAAAGUAGAUGAGAUAUCUCUUUUUUGGAAAUGGGAGUUUCACUCUUGUUGCCCACGCUGGAGUGCAAUGUGCAUUUUCCUUCAAAAUGCAGGAAAAAAGGAGGCAAGUCCAUCCAGAGAGGUGAAGUGACUUACCAAGCAAACCUAAGAAAACAAAAACCUUAGAAAACAUAAUUUUAUCAACCCCAAAGAUUUUAUUAAGAAAACAAAAAAAUUUAAGGAAUUAUAUUGUUAUGGCUUUGAGUUUGGGGUGUGAAAACAAUAUUGUGGUUAUGUUUAAAAAUAGAGUCCUCACCAUUGGGAGAUAUAUAUUGAAAUAUUUCUAGGUGAACGAUGCCUUGAAUUUGCUUUAAAACAACCAAUGGGGUGGAAGCAAACAGGUACAGGUAGAGAUGGGCCAAGAGUUGAUGAAUGAAGUUGCAUUAUAAGUACAUGGGAGGCCAGGCGCAGUGGCUCACGCCUGUAAUCCCAGCACUUCAGGAGGCCAAGGAAGGUGGAUCACAAGGUCAGGAGUUUGAGACCAGCCUGACCAACAUGGUAAAACCCGUUUCUACUAAAAAUACAAAAAUUAGCCAGGUGUGGUGGCACAUGCCUGUAAUCCCAGCUACUCAGGAGGCUGAGGCAGGAGAAUCACUUGAACCCAGGAGGCGGAGGUUGCAGUGAGCUGAGAUUGCAUCAUUCAUUGCACUCCAGCCUGGGCAACAGAGCAAGACUCUGCCUAAAAAAAAAAAAAAAAAGACAGUACAUGGGAUACUCUGGUUUCUCUUCAGAUCAUACAAAUCUCUCACCUUUUACUAAAGAUUUCUUCAGAGAGUAAUAAUUCUAAGUCUUAACCCAAUUUUUGAGGCCCUGCAUCUGCAAGGCUAGUAAGAAAGAAAAAAAAAAAAGUACAUGGGGUUCAUACUACUUUGUAGUUUUCGUUAAAUGAAACACUCUCACACAAAAGGUAUCUCCAGAAUUUACAAAAAUAUUUGGUACACAUUAGGUAAUCAAUAAACAUUUGUUAUAAAAAUAAAAUCCUGUUUACAACUAUGUAGUAAAGGAAAAGCAUACAGAAUGACAACCGAUAAAUUAAUGAAGUAGAACUACAUUUUUUCUCUUAUUUCCAAAAUGUUCUUAGUGCACAGGUUAUCUUAUAAUUUUUAAAACUAAAUGUUAAAAUAUUUGUUAGAGAUCAAGACAGUAAAAACUAAUUUAGUUCCUCAUUACUAUAGUUCCAUACUGACAAAUCUUUGAUUCUAACAGUCCCCAUUUAAGAGCUAACAAGUACCAGGUCAACAAGAGCUAAACUUAAUUCAAGAAUACUGAAACUUGAACUCACCAGCUUCUUUUGUGAAAUGGAAUAAUAACUGAUACCUUUGGGAGGGCUGAAUUUGUCUGUUUUUUUAAAUAUUUAUGUCUAUGGGUCACUCAGGUAUACGAAACACUUAAGACUAUCAUUUAUAACCCCAAGAUUAGGGUCUCUUCACAGAUCACUCUAACCUAAAAUUUUAUUAUCCUCAUUCUGAAAAUUGGCAUUAUUUGGUUUUCUUUCUCUACUAUUUUUCACUCAGCCACUAUUUCUGAUUCAGAUCACCUGUCAUCGAAGUUUAAAGAAGGGGAAACAGGAGACAGAAAUACACUGAACCAAAAAGAUUCAAAAGAGCAAGUGGAAUCUCUAAGAAUGGCUUCCAGCCACUGGAAUGAAACCACUACCUCUGUUUAUCAGUACCUUGGUUUUCAAGUUCAAAAAAUUUACCCUUUCCAUGACAACUGGAACACUGCCUGCUUUGUCAUCCUGCUUUUAUUUAUAUUUACAGUGGUAUCUUUAGUGGUGCUGGCUUUCCUUUAUGAAGUGCUUGACUGCUGCUGCUGUGUAAAAAACAAAACCGUGAAAGACUUGAAAAGUGAACCCAACCCUCUUAGAAGUAUGAUGGACAACAUCAGAAAACGUGAAACUGAAGUGGUCUAACACUCUAUAGAAGAUGAACAAAAUCUCUGAAAGCAGCUCAACCUCUUCUGAGAAAAAAAAUAUAUUCUGAGGCCAACUGUUGCUACAAAACAAAUUCUGACUGAAUGGUUAAAACAUUUCUAGUAGAAGGGGAAAAAAAAGUUAAACAUGCACUGUUUGUGUGUAUAGCCAUUUCAUUAAAUAUACAGUAAAACUUCAUGAAUGUGAAUUUACUAAUCUGUUUAAUACUGACACUUCAAAAACUGGAUAAAAGAUUCCUAGAGUUCAAUAUUAAGCAGCAAAAGAUAAGCUGGAAAAGACAAGCAAGGCUAAUGAUGCUAAAAUGAUUUUAUAACUAACCAAUUCAUGUAGACAAAAAAUAGUGUGUUGGUAACAAAAAGGCUAUUUAAAACAUGUUUCUAAGUCUGAAGUAAAAUACUUCCACUUAUAUAUAUAAAGUUCCUAUUUAUUAAAAAGUAGUAUUUUCU